AGAGACCCUUGACUGGGCCACAGGCAUGAACUAAGAGUGCUGAAGACCUAGGAGAACCACUGGUCAGGUCAGCUCCCAGCUCCACAGGGAGUAAGAAGGAGCUGCAGGCACAGCAGGCUGAAAGUCCACCAAGGGCUGAGGCCACAAGGCCUCUGGGGCAGCCACAGUUUUCAUGAUCACAUCAUACAGGACUGAGAAGCAGAUAACAAGAGUGACGCUCACAGGGGUAGGCAUAGACACACUGGGGCCGAAGGGGAGAGGAACUCUCCCUAGACACACAGAUUGCUCUCAGGCUGGGCUGACGCUAACAGGAGGCAGUGUGUGGCUCGAAGAUUCUUGAACCCACAGCAGCAGCUGCGGCCACCCCAUCCUGCCCACAGCUCCAGCCCUGAGACGACGAGGAGGAGAGUCGACUUUGCCUCUUGCCCAAGGGACCAUGCCCAGGUGCCGGUGGCUCUCCCUGAUCCUCCUCACCAUUCCCCUGGCCCUGGUGGCCAGGAAAGACCCAAAAAAGAAUGAGACAGGGGUGCUGAGGAAAUUAAAACCCGUCAAUGCCUCAAAUGCCAACGUGAAGCAGUGUCUGUGGUUUGCCAUGCAAGAAUACAACAAAGAGAGCGAGGACAAGUAUGUCUUCCUGGUGGUCAAGACACUGCAAGCCCAGCUUCAGGUCACAAAUCUUCUGGAAUACCUUAUUGAUGUAGAAAUUGCCCGCAGCGAUUGCAGAAAGCCUUUAAGCACUAAUGAAAUCUGCGCCAUUCAAGAAAACUCCAAGCUGAAAAGGAAAUUAAGCUGCAGCUUUUUGGUAGGAGCACUUCCCUGGAAUGGUGAAUUCACUGUGAUGGAGAAAAAGUGUGAAGAUGCUUAAUGGUGUUUUGAGGCAUCCCUCCAACCUCUGUGACUACUUUAUCCAUGAAAAUGAAGCAAUGGCAGGUACGUGCAAAUGAAGAUGUGGCUCCCACCCACGGGACUGGAGGAAAUCAACAAGGGCGGAAGUACAGGAGAGACAGAGAUGUCUGAGGACUGCGCCCCGCCACUCUCAGGUGAGAGGCGGCAGGCAAGAGCCCUGAGGCCACAGAGACGUGCUGUCCUCGAAGGGAGGGAGUGCCCACCUGUGCCAGUCAUGGCGGGCGGGUCAAGGAGGAUGCACGCUCAGAGCCGACCACGGGUUCAACCUUCCCACGUCAUUGCUCACCCUGGUGAGAGCAUGGAACAGACUGGAGUAGGUUCCAGAGAGUGCAGGAAGAGGGGAAUUGGAGACCAUGAGGACAGACACUUCUUUUGAAAGAUUUUGCUGUAAAGUGCCAUCAACACAGGGUCCCAAGAGUUCUCAGCCACAUCAGCUCCAAGAAGAACUUGUUUCAUUGAGGAUUUAGGGGAACUGUCUCAUUGGCGAAGAGAAGUUCUCCUCCCCCUGCCCCGAUGUGACUCGUUAAGGUUUGGGGUGCCCUGGCUCUUGGAGCUUUCAUCUAUGGUCUAAACCUUGAACACCAUAAACAUUAGGUUGGCAGUUCUUGGAGCUUGGGUAACUGCAUGCACAUGCCUUGUUCACACAUGUCCCAGUAUUUUUACUUACUCUGUUGAGGGAGUUUAUUCUUUCCUUUGAAUACAUUUCACUCCCACCUGUAAUAAACUCCCAAUUGGUCUUUCUA